ACUUCCAACAUGGCGGCGGCCGGGGCGGCGGUGGCGCGCAGCCCGGGAAUCGGAGCGGGACCUGCGCUGAGAGCCCGGCGCUCGCCCCCGCCGCGGGCCGCACGGCUGCCGCGGCUGCUAGUGCUGCUAGCGGCGGCGGCGGUGGGGCCGGGCGCGGGCGGUGCGGCGCGGCUGUACCGCGCGGGCGAGGACGCCGUGUGGGUGCUGGACAGCGGCAGCGUGCGCGGGGCCACCGCCAACAGCUCGGCCGCGUGGCUCGUGCAGUUCUACUCGUCGUGGUGUGGCCACUGCAUCGGCUACGCGCCCACUUGGCGGGCCCUGGCUGGGGAUGUGCGAGACUGGGCCAGUGCCAUUCGCGUCGCAGCUCUGGACUGCAUGGAAGAGAAGAACCAGGCCGUGUGCCAUGACUACGACAUCCACUUCUACCCCACCUUCCGGUAUUUUAAAGCAUUUACAAAGGAGUUUACAACUGGAGAAAAUUUUAAAGGACCUGACCGAGAGCUGCGAACAGUCAGACAGACGAUGAUUGACUUCCUGCAGAACCACACGGAAGGAAGCCGGCCCCCUGCCUGCCCGCGCCUAGACCCCAUUCAGCCCAGUGAUGUUCUUUCCCUUCUUGACAACCGUGGCAGCCAUUACGUGGCUAUUGUCUUUGAAAGCAACAGCUCCUACCUUGGACGGGAGGUGAUCUUAGACCUGAUCCCGUAUGAAAGCAUCGUGGUGACCCGAGCACUGGACGGGGACAAAGCAUUUCUGGAGAAACUUGGUGUUUCUUCAGUCCCUUCGUGUUACCUGAUCUACCCAAAUGGGUCGCAUGGAUUGAUUAACGUCGUGAAGCCUCUGCGGGCCUUCUUUUCGUCUUAUUUGAAGUCAUUGCCGGAUGUGAGGAAAAAAUCGCUUCCCUUGCCUGAAAAGCCACACAAAGAAGAAAAUUCAGAAAUCGUGGUUUGGAGAGAAUUUGACAAGUCGAAGCUGUACACGGUGGACCUGGAGUCAGGGCUACACUACCUCCUGCGGGUGGAGCUGGCAGCCCACAAGUCCCUGGCCGGAGCAGAGCUGAAGACGCUCAAGGACUUUGUGACUGUCUUGGCCAAGCUGUUCCCUGGACGGCCGCCAGUCAAGAAGCUGUUGGAGAUGCUGCAGGAGUGGCUGGCCAGCCUUCCCCUGGACAGGAUCCCCUACAACGCCGUGCUUGACCUGGUCAACAACAAGAUGCGGAUUUCUGGAAUAUUCCUUACUAAUCACAUAAAGUGGGUUGGAUGUCAAGGAAGCCGAUCUGAGUUGAGGGGUUACCCGUGUUCUCUCUGGAAACUGUUCCACACUUUGACUGUUGAAGCCUCGACCCACCCAGAUGCACUGGUUGGCACAGGCUUUGAAGACGACCCCCAGGCUGUGCUGCAGACAAUGAGGAGGUACGUUCACACCUUCUUUGGGUGUAAGGAAUGUGGUGAGCACUUUGAGGAAAUGGCUAAAGAAUCCAUGGACUCGGUGAAAACCCCAGACCAAGCCAUCCUCUGGCUGUGGAAGAAGCAUAAUAUGGUGAACGGCCGCCUGGCAGGCCAUCUGAGUGAGGAUCCCCGGUUUCCAAAGCUUCAGUGGCCCACUCCGGACCUCUGCCCAGCCUGCCAUGAGGAAAUUAAGGGCCUGGCCAGCUGGGAUGAAGGCCACGUGCUCACAUUCUUGAAGCAGCACUAUGGCCGCGACAACCUCUUAGACACGUAUUCCGCAGACCAGGGGGAUUCCAGUGAAGGAGGAACCCUGGCCAGGGGUGAGGAAGAGGAGAAAAGACUCACUCCCCCAGAGGUGUCCCAUGGAGACCGAGACACCCAGAGCGUCCGUCCACCUGGUGCACUGGGCCCCAGGCCUGCCCUUCCAGAGAGCUUGCAUCACAGCUUGGACGGGAAACUCCAGAGUCUGGAUGGGCCCGGGGCCCACAAGGAGGUGGGCGGGGCCGCACCCUUCCUCGGGGUUGACUUCUCCAGCCUGGACAUGAGUCUCUGUGUCGUGCUGUACGUGGCUUCAUCCCUGUUCCUCAUGGUGAUGUACUUCUUCUUCCGGGUGAGGUCCAGGCGGUGGAAGGUCAAGCACCACCACCCGGCCGUGUGAGUGCCCGGGUGCUGCCAGCCACGGCGGAAGCUCCCUUGGAGGCAGCCCUGCCCCGUGCCACCUGCAGCUUUAAUAUUUAUGAUCAGGGAUUUUAUAAACAUGCGGGCCUGGUUUCACAUCGGAUGGCACCUUUUGGCUUCAAAGUCCUGGUUUUACAAACGCUCUUCUAACAAGGGAAGAACACGGGGUAAUUUUGUGGGGAUAUUUGCAUUCCUGGCGUACUCAAGUCUGUUCAUGCUCCUUUUGCAGGUCUUACAGCAAAAAGACUUCUGUAUUUUUACUCUUCUAGAUGUGAAAAGAGGGUGCAGAGUCCAGGCCAGAUAGUCUUCCCCACACACUUUCAUCUCGUUUCCUCCACUCCGCCCCAUCCUGCAGGGCCUUGUUUUUGUAUUUGGAGAACCUCGCCCAUCCCCCCCGCGGCUCCUGGCUCCCCCCCACUCCCCUCGCUCCCCCUCCCCCCGCUCCCCCCACGCCCCCUGCUCCAGGCUGCCAAGUGUUUUCCUUUAGCCGGGCGGGGACAGACAGAGCCGGAAGCGCAGUCGGCCUCUGCAGCCCCUCCAAGCAAGUGCUCCAGGGACUAUCCUGUGUUUGUAGCUGCUUCCCUAGGGCAGGUUCCUGAGGGCUCUCCUUGUUCCUCCGGGUGUUCGACACCAGACGUGGGGAUUUCAACAGGGGAGGAGCCAAGGAAUUCUGUGGCUGUGCUGCGUUUCAGAAAAUAACCCCCAGAGGCCUUGGGCUGUGGACCUGGGGGUUGGAAGGAUGGGGGCUCAUUUAACCCUCAGAGGCAGCGCCUUUGUCUGUCUAUCUGGUGACAAGAGAGAGACAAGUAAAUGGGGGCCGUUGGGACGGCGGGUGCCUGGAGGGCAGCUCUGGGCUCAGCGGGCAGUGCUUAGAGCACAGGCCCCUCUGUUGGGGGAUGGGGAGGAGAGCAGUCUGCCCUUGGGAGCGUAGGCCCCAGGGAGACUUCUAAAGCCCCCCCUGUCGUCUGCUCUUCACCCAGCACCACAGAGGCACCUGCUGCACACACAAGCAUCUCACUCGGCCCACGGAGGGGGCCAGGCUUCCUUUGCCUGAAGCUGUUUUGGGAAGGGUCUCCACACAGGCACUGAUCUCCCAAGCUUUUGUCAUGAUGUCUUUUACCAUUUGAUAAUUUUAAACAUUGUUUUUAAACCCAAAACAUUUAGUGGUCCGUUGCCUCUGAAGAUGUAAACAAACAAAUACACUAUUUCUGGGAACAUUUAUAUUGAGAUUCUUUGUGGCUAUUGGUGUGUCUCACAGGCAAAAUUUGAUUUGGCUAAAAUAGGCUCAGAUGUAUUUGUGUGCCCGUGUGUGUGUGUGUGUGUGUGUGUGUGUGUGUGUGUGUAUGAGAGAGAGAGAGACUUUGACGGUUGUAGAUAUUUUUUCCGCUUUGCCUACUUUAUGUUGUAUAAUCAUGUGUUUACUAACAAGUUGAUGACAUGGAUGUAUUCAUAAGACCAUGUAAUAUUGAUGUGAUUGUUGUCGCUUGAGAAAAAAAGGCAACAGCUGAUUCUUUCAACAACUGUCACAGAAUGGCUGGGCUGAGAACGCUGCCCAGGGCCCUGCAGCUGGCGGGAGAGGUGUCUGGUGGGAGCGGUGUCUGGUGCGUCAGCCUGCUGCUUCGUGUCUCACUCGAGAGUUGCUUCUGGUUUCACACUUUUUAACCCCUCUGUGCUUUAGCAGCCGUGACCUUGCCUUCAUUGCUUCAUCCAGUGCAGGCCUGGGUUAUUGAAGACACCAAAGUGUUUCUCUUCCAGUUUGAAAACCAGGCAGGUUUACACGUGGGUUUCAGUGUAUUUGCCUUUGAACCCUUCAAACUAAACUUUAGCCUUUUGGCUGGUGUUGAAUGUCUUUAGCUGGGGUGACCUGGAGUGACCUGGGACGGUGUUGUGGUUUACCGUCUCCAGCUUCAGCCUUUCCAGAAACCCUUGUGGAGGGCAGUGUUGGCUGCAGGUUUCAUCAUAUUGCAGUUUGAGGUCACCACUAUUUGGGGAACAAGCUUGCGUCCUGCUGAGGGGCAGGAUUUUCAGCAGAGCGUCGGUGGGGCUGGGCCGUCGUGGAGGUGGCCCCAGGAGUCAUAUGGCCAUACUCAGACACACCUUGUGUGGCCUGCUCAGAGCUGGAUGCCACCUUUAGGCAAUGUUUAGAGUCUAUUUUCUAAAGUUUUAAGUAUUUUAAGAGGUAUUGAGACUAAUGAAUAUAAUAGUUCAGUAAUUUAAAUGCUUAUUUAUUUUCAGUGGAAGGAUUUUUAUUAAAAAGAAGCUAAUUGACAUGGAAAUGUCAGUGAAAUUUCUUACCUGCAAGGAAAGUGAACAUUUUGUAUUUAAGUAAACUAUAAUGUGCACAUUUUAAUAAAGAAAUCUGACAUUUGAAAAAA